AGAGCCGAUCAGGUGUCAGAGUGGAGCGGCUGGAGCUGCUCGUGGCCCAGCUGGGAGUGGGUAACCGGAGCCGGCAGUGGGCACUGUGGCCGGGAGCUCGGGGCACUGGAGCUGCAGGAGCCCACGGAUUGUCUUCUCCCAAGCAGCCUGUGAACUCCUCUGUUGGGUGUCUUAUUACCCCCUGCUUUGGGUGUGAUUGAAUCCUCCAGUCAGAGGUAGAAGAAAAAAGGGUGGCCUGUGGAGAGGAGAAACACAGGGCACCAACUAUGAAGACUCUCAGGGCGCGAUUUAAGAAGACAGAGCUGCGGCUCAGCCCCACUGACCUUGGCUCCUGCCCGCCCUGCGGCCCCUGCCCCAUCCCGAAGCCGGCAGCCAGAGGCAGGCGCCAGAGUCAAGACUGGGGCAAGAGUGACGAGAGGCUGCUACAAGCCGUGGAAAACAACGAUGCACCUCGGGUGGCCGCCCUCAUCGCCCGCAAGGGGCUGGUGCCCACGAAGCUAGACCCCGAGGGCAAGUCCGCGUUCCACCUGGCGGCCAUGCGGGGUGCGGCCAGCUGUCUGGAGGUGAUGAUAGCUCAUGGCAGCAAUGUCAUGAGCGCGGACGGGGCAGGUUACAAUGCCCUCCACCUGGCCGCCAAAUACGGGCACCCACAGUGCUUGAAGCAACUACUGCAGGCUUCCUGCGUGGUGGACGUCGUGGACAGCAGCGGGUGGACUGCCCUACACCAUGCAGAGACAGGGUCUCACUGUGUUGGCCCAGCGGCUGGUGGCUGUCUCUCCUGCUCAGAGGUGCUCUGCUCCUUUAAGGCACAUCUAAACCCCCAAGAUCGGUCAGGCGCAACACCCCUCAUUAUAGCAGCUCAGAUGUGUCACACAGACCUGUGCCGUCUCCUACUGCAGCAAGGGGCUGCCGCGAACGAUCAGGACCUGCAAGGCAGGACGGCCCUGAUGCUGGCCUGUGAGGGGGCCAGCCCCGAAACAGUGGAGGUCCUGCUGCAGGGCGGAGCCCAGCCGGGCAUCACCGAUGCGCUGGGGCAGGACGCGGCUCACUAUGGCGCCCUGGCGGGGGACAAACUCAUCCUGCACCUUCUGCAAGAGGCGGCCCAGCGCCCCUCCCCACCCAGCGCCCUCACAGAGGAUGAUUCAGGCGAGGCGUCAUCUCAGAACUCUAUGUCCAGCCAUGGAAAGCAGGGGGCCCCCAAGAAGCGGAAGGCGCCUCCACCUCCCGCCAGCAUUCCCAUGCCGGAUGAUCGAGAUGCCUAUGAGGAGAUCGUGAGGCUGCGGCAGGAGAGGGGCCGCCUCCUGCAGAAGAUCCGGGGCCUGGAACAGCACAAGGAACGGAGGCAGCAGGAGCCACCUGGGCCUCCUCGCUGUUCCUCCAACUCGCCAGGCGCAGUCCUGCCUCAGGGCCUUUGCACCACCAGUGUCCUCUGCCUGGAAUGCUCUAGCGCAGUCCUGCCUCAGGGCCUUUGCACCACCUGUGUCCUCUGCCUGGAAUGCUCUAGCCCCAGAUGGCCCCACAGCUCUUUACCUCACCUACUUUAUGCAUCCCCGGAGGCCAGCUCCCUGCACAUCCUGGAGAGACAGGUGCAAGAGCUACAGCAGUUGCUGGUGGAGAGACAAGAGGAGAAGGAGAGCCUGGGACGGGAGGUGGAGAGUUUGCAGAGCCGGCUGUCCCUGCUGGAGAACGAGCGGGAGAAUACUAGCUAUGACGUAACCACCCUGCAGGAUGAGGAGGGUGAGCUGCCUGACCUUCCAGGGGCCGAGGUGCUGCUGUCCAGACAACUCAGUCCGUCGGCCCAGGAACACCUGGCCUCGCUGCAGGAACAGGUGGCUGUGCUCACCAGACAGAACCAGGAACUGAUGGAGAAGGUCCAGAUCCUGGAGAACUUUGAGAAGGACGAGACACAGAUGGAAGUGGAAGCUUUGGCAGAGGUCAUCCCUCUUGCCCUCUAUGACUCUCUCCGGGCCGAGUUUGACCAGCUACGCAGGCAGCACGCUGAGGCCCUGCAGGCCCUGAGGCAGCAGGAGACACGAGAGGUCCCCAGAGAAGAGGGGGCAGCCUGUGGGGAGAGUGAGGUUGCUGGAGCCACGGCCACCAAAAACGGGCCAACCCACAUGGAGCUAAAUGGCUCAGUGGCUCCAGAAACCAAAGUUAACGGAGCCGAGACCAUAGAUGAGGAGGCUGCAGGAGAUGAAACCAUGGAAGCCAGGACUAUGGAAGCUGAGGCCACGGGAGCCGAGGCCACGGGAGCUGAGGCCACAGGAGCCAAGGUCACAGAAACAAAACCCACAGGGGCUGAGGUCAGAGAAAUGGAGACCACAGAAGAAGAAGCAAACAUGGAAACUAAGCCCACAGGAGCUCAGGCCACAGACACAGAGACCACGGGAGUGGAGGCCAUGGGGGUGGAGGCCACAAAAACAAAAGCAGAGGAAGCAGAAAUGCAGGCCUACGGAGUGGGUGCUGGGCAAGCAGAGCCCCCAGUCACAGGGACCACAAACAUGGAGGCCACGGGCUCUAGGGCCACAGGGAUGGAAUCCACAGGAGUCAGUGCCACAGGUGUGGAGAACCCAGGGGUAGAGGCCACGGUCCCGGGGAUCUCUGCUGGCCCCAUCCUACAUCCUGGUGCCGCAGAGGCCUCGGAAAAGCUUCAAGUAGAGCUGGAGACCAGGAUCCGUGGCUUGGAGGAGGCUCUCCGGCAGCGGGAGCGGGAGGCAGCUGCGGAGCUGGAGGCGGCCCUGGGGAAGUGCGAGGCCGCGGAGGCCGAGGCAGGCCGGCUGCGAGAGCGUGUCCGCGAGGCCGAGGGCAGCGGGGCCAGCGGGGGCGGUGGCGGUGACACCACACAGCUGCGGGCGGCCCUGGAGCAGGCCCGGGAGGACCUCCGAGACCGGGACUCCCGCCUGCGGGAGCUGGAGGCGGCCUCGGCCUGCCUGGAUGAGGCUCGGGCCAGCCGGCUGCUGGCGGAGGAGGAGGCGCGGGGCCUGCGGGCCGAGCUGGCCCAGCGGGAGGAGGCGCGGCUGGAGCAGAGCCGGGAGCUGGAGGUUCUGCGGGAGCAGCUGGCCACGGCCAGGGCCACGGGGGAGCAGCAGCGCACGGCGGCCGCGGAACUGGGCCGGGCACGGGACGCCGCUGAGGCCCGAGUGGCUGAGCUGCCUGCGGCCUGCGAGGAGGCGCGGCAGGGCCUGGCCGAGCUGCGGGAGGCCUCCGAGGCCCUCCGCCAGUCCGUGGUGCCGGCCUCUGAGCACCGCCGGCUGCAGGAGGAGGCCCUGGAGCUGCGGGGCCGGGCAGCCAGUCUGGAGCAGGAGGUGGUGGCCACGGGCAAGGAGGCCGCCCGGCUGCGCGCGGAGCUGGAGCGGGAGCGUGUGUGCAGCGUGGCGCUCUCGGAGCACGAACGCAUCGUGGGCACCCUGCAGGCCAACGUGGCCCAGCUGGAGGGGCAGCUGGAGGAGCUGGGACGGCGGCAUGAGAAGACCAGCGCAGAGGUCUUCCAGGUGCAGCGUGAGGCCCUGUUCAUGAAGAGUGAGCGACACGCAGCCGAGGCACAGCUGGCCACAGCAGAGCAGCAGCUACGGGGGCUACGGACCGAGGCGGAAAGGGCUCGCCAGGCCCAGAGCCGGGCCCAGGAGGCUCUGGACAAGGCCAAGGAGAAGGACAAGAAGAUCACAGAACUCUCCAAAGAAGUCUUCAAUCUUAAGGAAGCCUUGAAGGAGCAGCCGGCCGCCCUCGCCACCCCUGAGGUGGAGGCUCUCCGUGACCAGGUGAAGGAUUUACAGCAGCAGCUGCAGGAAGCUGCCAGGGACCACUCCAGCGUGGUGGCUUUGUACAGAAGCCACCUCCUAUAUGCCAUUCAGGGCCAGAUGGAUGAAGAUGUGCAGCGGAUUCUCAGCCAGAUUCUGCAGAUGCAGAGACUCCAGGCUCAGGGCCGCUGAGAAAGGCCAGGCCCAGUGGCUACACUGACCACACCCACGCAGGGACCUCACCCCCCUGCAGGCCCCUUGCAGACCGGCUUCACUUGGCUUCACUUGGCCCUAUCCAGGCCCAUGCACUUGGAGACCAGCCUGGUUCCCUGCCCGACCACCCCCAGCUGGCUCCAUCACCCCACCUGGUCUCUGCACGCACACACUGGUCAGUCUGGACCCGGGCCGUGACUGCCCCUCCCCCACCACCGGAGACUGUGAUUCCCUGUGUCCUCCACAUCCAGACGCCAGCCCAGGAAUAAAGGCAUUCUGUGCACAGGG